GCAGUUGCUGAAAUGGAGGCAGAGGUGUGGGAGGCAGAAGGCUACAACCUAGUUCUGGACUCGGACCUGUAUGAUGCGGAUGGCUAUGAUGUCCCAGACCCUGGGCUGCUCACCGAAAAGAAUGUUCCUGCCCGCAGAGUUGACUUUCACGGAGCCGUCGCAGGUCCUGCCCUUUUUGACCAGCAGCCAACAGUGGCAAAGCCUGACCCCGCGCGCCCGCGCCCGCCGGCUGUGGCUGCUUCUGCGCACCAGCCUCCACGAAGUCGUGGAAAAGGAGAAGAGAGCCGAGCUGCGCGCGGCGCGCCUGACGCAUGGGCUGGAACCACUGCGCCGCCUGGAGGUGGCAGCCGGGCUGCGCUCGGUGGCGCAGGACCCGGUGGGUGGACGCUUCGUGGUGCUGGACGGCGCGGGCCGCCUGCACCUGCACAAGGAAGACGGCUGGGCACAGGAGACGCUGCUGGCGCCUGUCCGGCUUACGGGGCUGGUGACCGUGCUGGGCCCGCUGGGUGCCGUGGGCCGUUUUGUAGGCUGGGGCCCCGCGGGGCUGGCAAUUCUGAGGCCCAACCUCAGCCUGCUGUGGCUGAGCGAGCAGGGGGUGGGCAGGGCCCCGGGUUGGGCGCCCACCUGCUGCCUGCCGGUUCCCGACCUCAGGCUGCUGCUCGUUGCGGAGAUGAACAGCAGCCUGGCGCUCUGGCAGUUCCGUUCAGGUGGUCGCCGCCUGGUGCUGCGAGGGUCAGCACUGCACCCGCCCCCGAGCCCAACAGGCAGGCUCAUGCGUCUGGCUGUGGCGCCGGUUCCUCCCCACCACGUCCUGCGCUGCUUCGCGGCCUAUGGCUCGGCCGUGCUCACCUUCGAUCUGCAUGCCUGGACUCUCGUAGAUGUGCGCCGGGAUUUGCACAAAACCACCAUCUCGGACCUGGCUUACUGCGAGGAAGUAGAGGCAAUGGUGACAGCUUCCCGGGACAGCACCGUGAAGGUGUGGGAGGCUGACUGGCAGAUCCGGAUGGUGUUCGUGGGCCACACAGGCCCGGUGACGGCUAUGACUGUGCUCCCGAACACGACCCUGGUGUUGUCGGCCUCGCAGGACGGGACGCUACGCACCUGGGACCUGCAGGCGGCGGCGCAGGUGGGCGAGGUAGCGCUGGGCUUCUGGGGCCAGGACAAGCUGUCCCGGCGCGUGGGCCGUCUGCUGGCGCCGGUGCGCCCGGGCUGGCCGGUGCUGUCCCUGUGCGCGAGCAGCAUGCAGCUGUGGCGCGUACGCGAGCUCUACUCGCCGUUGGCGCAACUGCCCGCCAAGGUGCUCCACGUGCAGGUGGCGCCCGCGUUGCCCGCGCCUGCGCACCAGUCGCUGCCUACGCGCCUCGUGUGCGCGUGCGCCGACGGCUCGGUCUACCUCCUGUCGGCGGCCACCGGGCGCAUAGUGAGCUCACUGCUGCUGGAGCCGGAGGACUGCGCGGCAGCCGUGGCCUACUGCCUGCCGCGCGAGGCGCUGUGGCUGCUGACCAGGGCUGGGCACCUGGUCCGCGCCAACGCGGCGCGCUGCCCCAUGAGCGUGCUGCACCGCGUGUGCCCGCCGCCGCCCCCUGCGCCGCAGCCUUGCUGUCUGCACCUGUACAGCCACCUCACGGAUCUCGAAGGCGCCUUCUCCUCCUGGGAGAUCGUGCGCCAGCACUGGGGCGAGUUGCGCUGCAGCUCUGUGGCCUGCGCCUGGAAGAACAAGAACCGGUACCUGCCAGUGGUGGGGCACACGGACGGCACGCUGUCGGUGCUGGAGUGGCUCUCGUCGAAGACUGUCUUCCAAACGGAGGCGCACAGCCCGGGCCCGGUUGUCGCCAUCGCAUCCACCUGGAACAGCAUUGUGUCUUCGGGUGGGGACCUGACGGUGAAGAUGUGGCGCGUCUUCCCCUAUGCCGAAGAGAGCCUGAGCCUGCUGCGCACCUUCUCCUGCUGCUACCCGGCCGUGGCGCUCUGUGCGCUAGGCAGACGCGUCACCGCGGGCUUUGAGGACCCAGACAGCGCUACCUACGGCCUGGUGCAGUUUGGCCUGGGCGACAGUCCGCGAUUAGACCACCGGCCCCAGGACGACCCCACGGACCACAUCACUGGCCUGUGCUGCUGCCCCACGCUCAAACUGUAUGCCUGCUCCAGCCUGGACUGCACCGUUCGCAUCUGGACUGCUGAGAACCGCCUCCUGCGGCUCCUGCAGCUGAAUGGUGCCCCUCAGGCCCUGGCUUUCUGCAGCAACAGUGGAGACCUGGUGCUGGCGCUGGGAUCCCGCCUCUGCCUGGUGUCCCACAGGCUCUACCUGCCUACAUCCUACCUAGUUAAGAAGAUGUGCCGGAAGGCCCCAGACGUGGUGGACGACCCUCCGCUGCCACUGAUGAGCCAGGAGUCACUGACUUCCGCCCAACUGCAGAGGCUCACCAACCUCCAUGGGGCAGCCAGCCUCAGCGAGGCCUUGUCUCUCAUCCAUCGUCGGAGGGCAACAUCUCAGCACCUGGUGCCGAAGGAGGACUUGGACGCCAUAGUGGCCCGGGACCGAGACCUUCAGCAGUUGAGGCUGGGGCUAGUGGUCCCAGCAGCCCAGCCCCCACCCUCCUGGCAGCAGCGCCAGGAAGGCUUUGACAAUUACCUCCGUCUGAUCUACGGCUCUGGCCUGCUGGGCAUGCAGUCUGGAAGGGGGUCCCAGCAGUGGAGUGCCGGGACCCUCAGAGUGGAGAGAGAGACCCGGGAUGUGUGUGCUGUACCCCAAGCUGCCCACUGUCUUGCCCGGGCUGAGGUCAGCACUGCAGCCCAAACAGUGCCAACAGCCCUGUCCCCACAGGACCUGGGAGCCCUGGGCCAGCACUUCUCCCAGUCUCCCCGAGUCACAGUGCCGAUCCCACCCACCCACCGUAGGGUGCACAGCAAGGCAUCCCAGCUUCUGGCCCGCUCCUCACUGAGCCACUACCUGGGCAUCAGUCUGGAUCUGCAGCUGCAGUUGGAGCAGCUCCGAGGGAGGACGACCAUGGCCCUGGACCUGCCAUCCUCCCACUUGCAGUGCAGGAUCCCACUGCUGCCAAAGAGAUGGGACAAGGAACCUCUCUCUAGCCUCAGGGGCUUCUUUCCUGCCACCGUGCAGCCCCACAAGCACUGCCUGAGGCCCAUCUGCUUCCCCGGCUAUGUGCCCAACUCCGCGGUGCUACAGCAGAUGUGGCUAAAUGCGGAGGUCAGCAGCCUCGGAUCCCCGACUCAGCUCGCCUCCCAGAGAAAGCUCGAGCCAGGGGCAAGCCAGGAUGCCCUGUGGUUGUGGCGCCCCAGGCCAUCCCAAACCCAGUGGCAGAGGAAGCUGCUCCAAUGGAUGGGGGAGAAGCCUGGGGAGGAGGGGGAGGAAGACAAGAAGGAAGAGGAGGAGGAGAAGGAAGACGAGGAGCUGGACUGGGCCUUGGCUUCCCUGAGCCCGCACUCCAACCAGCAGCUGGAUUCCUGGGAACUGGAGGAUCAGAGUGCUGUGGACUGGACCCAGGAGCCCCGGCGGCGCAGCUGCAAGGUUGCCAGGACCCACCCUCAUCCCUGGCACCGUCAUGGGAGUUUGCUCUUGGAUGAGCAUUACGGGCAUCUGCCCAAGUUUCUGCAUUUCUUCAUCUACCAGACCUGGUUCAAAAAGUUGUUCCCCAUCUUCAGCCUGCAGGCAUACCCGGAGGCGGGCACGAUCGAGGGCCUGGCCUCGCUGUUGGUGGCCCUGCUGGAGAAGACCACGUGGGUCGACCGUGUGCACAUCCUGCAGGUGCUACUGAGACUGCUGCCCAACAUGAGCAGUGAUCUCCAAGGCCAGCUGCAGGGCCUGCUCGUACACUUGCUCAACCUGGACCAGCCCCCCAGCCUCCAGGUGUGCCCCUUGUCCUGCCCCCAGUUUUCCUCCCCGCCCACCGGCCCUCAGCAACCACAUCCCCACCGCCUGCCUCAGGACCAGACACAGAAGAAGUUCGUGAUACUGGCGCUGCAGCUGCUCCUGGCCUGCUCCCUGGAGUCCCGGGAUGUGGUGCUGGAGCUCAUGUCCUACUUCCUCUACUCUCCCGUGCACUGCCGGCCAGAGCUCAAGAAGCUGCUGCACGGGCUGGGCCUUCAGGACCCAGAGGGCUUCCUAUUCAAGGAGAUGAUGACCUGGGUCCAGGGCCCAGACCUGGACUCCAAGGCCGGCCUGCGCACUUGCUGCCACCAGAAACUGGAGGACAUGAUCCAGGAGCUUCAGGAGACCCCAUCGCAGACGUCAGUGGUCUCUGGGGCACCCACACGCGCCUCCGUGAUACCCUCGGGCACCUCCUGGUCGGCCUCCGGCAUCUUCGGGAGGCUCUCGCAGGUCUCAGAGGUGCCUUUGAUGGUGGUCUCACCUGCGGAGCCGCACUCUUUAGCCCCGGAGCUCCAGGCCCAGCGGAUGCUGGCACCCAAGCGCAGCUGGGGGACCCCUCAGCUCCGUCUCAGAGUGCUCUCCGAGACGCUGAAGAGCUUCUGCCUGGAGCCCGAGGCCCGCCUGCACCCUGCCGGGCCUGCUCAGCUGCCCGGAGAGCCGCCGCCGCUGGAGGAGACCGACUGGUCGCACUCGCAGCUGCUGGACUUGGGCCCCAUCGACGCGCUCAACUUCUUCUGUGAGCAGCUGCGGGCGCAGCAGCGGAGUUCGCUCCAGGAGAAGGCUGCGCACCCACACCCGCCAGAGCCCUACACGGUGGCGCCGGUGCCCGACAUGGUGGUGCCACCUCCGCGGGAGCACUGGUACCACCCCAUCCUCCGGCUGCAGGAGGCCAAGCCGCAGAGGUCCGCGAGGUCCGCGAUGAGACUGAGGGGCCCCAUGCGGUCCCGGCUCUGUGCGGGCCGCACCCUGGACGGCCCCAUCCGGACGCUGAAGCUGCCGUUGCCGCGUGUGGAGCCGCAGCCUUUCCCCCUGGACUGGCCUAUGCCCCCGCGCCCGCUGCCCCCGCGGCUCCUGCAGCCGGCCCUGCAGCGCUACUUUCUGCCAGCGGACGCGGACCCUGACACCUACAGCUGACCGGACUGGUGGCCUCAGCCCGCCUGGCUCUGGGGCCUGUCAUUGGUAUUUGGCCAAGGCCUGCAUCGGGAAUAAAGUCCAGAGAAUUUCUUUCUGCAGGAUGCCGCCUGCUUUGGAGGGCCCCGGGGUGCGCACGGCGUGUGGGCGUGCGGCCUGAACCCACAGUGGCGGCGGAAGGCAGGAGCCGGAGGCCUGGCGGAGGUGGCCAUCGUGGGCACCAGCGUUCCCGGAGGGGUGGCCGGCCUAGGGCAGAGGAGACCCAUAGCGGGGUACCAUCCGCUGGGCACUGAGCAAACGUUUUCUGCUCAAGUACUAGGUGUUGAGAUGCGGGCUGACCUUAGAGAACGUGUCCUGGGCCAGCCCACAGCCUGGUGUGGAGGGGAGUCCGGGAGGGCCUGGGCGGUCCCAGGAUGAGCCUUCCGGGUCGAUGCAGGUGAGACCAGGAGUUUGCAGACCUUGCUUUCGUUACUUUUAUUCUGGCAAAGAGAAGAAUUGACAAAGGCACCAGGAGCUUUUUUCUGAGCGGCAACGCAGAGCAUCCUCUGACCCCUUUAGCCUGAAAGUCCCUAGGGGAGGGGCUUGGUCCGGAAGGGCUCGGCCUCUGGGCCGGGCCCCUCUGCCCUGUGUGGCCUGGCAGGGCGCAAGACCUGUGCACAGAGUUCUUGGGGCAGCUCUGGGGGGAAUCCCCGGCUUUUACACCUGUCUUUUGUGUUGUCUGAGCAGUGAUUUCCCUCCUGUAUCUGUAGCCUCUGACUUUACUAGUUUCUUCUUGAUGGCUCUGGUUAGAAUCGCUUCUCCACACCUUCCCUGUCACCCCAAACUGUGCGGUGGCUCUUGUUAUGGGGCCACCAAAUGGCUGCUCUUUCCCAGGCCGGUGCUUGACACAGUGGUGCCACCAUCCCAAGAGCAUGGGUGCGCAGGACCGUGCGGGACAGCCAAGUUGCUGGGCCCAGCUGAACCUGCCUCUUCACCUCCAGGCACUACCGCAUCCUCCCACUGCAGAAGGCCAAGGUUCACAGGUGUGCGAUGAGACUGAGGACUGAGUCUGUCACUAGAGGACUUGACACUUUUUAUAAAAAAAAUGAGUAAACCUAGAUACCUCGAUCAGUGUCUAGCGAUGUCAAGGCCCCCAGUUUGGGUUCAAGCCUGCUGGGACAGUCCUGCAGCUGCUGGGUCACAGAGUGGCCAAGGCCCUCUGAUUUUUGGUCAGGACACAGAAAGAUAGCAGGGGGCAGGGGGGGAUCUGAGGGACCCCACAUGACUUACAAUCAGACAAGGUAGGUCAGAGGAUUUCUUUAUGGCUAUCUGUUUUGUUUUGUUUUGUUUUGUUUUGUUUUUUGAGAUGGAGUUUCAGUCUUGUUGCCCAGGCUGGAGUGCAAUGGCGUGAUCUCGGCUCACUGCAACCUCUGCCUCCCGGAUUCAAGCAAUUCUCCUUCCUCAGCCUCCUGAGUAGCUGGGAUUACAGGCAUGUGCCACCACGCCCAGCUAAUUUUGUAUUUUUAGUAGAGAUGGGGUUUCAUCACGUUGACCAGGCUGGUCUCGAACUCCUGACCUCAGGUGAUCCGCCUGCCUCAGCCUCUCAAAGUGCUGGGAUUACAAGCAUGAGCCACUGUGCCCAGCCUUCUUUAUGGCUAUCUCCAAGACAGCAAAGGCAGGGGAAAGUCCUGCCUUGGGGAGAAAAAGGAGGGUGGGAAAAGGUCAAAGAGAAAGAUGCUGUUGUCUGAGUCUUGCCUCUGAGGCCUAAGUUCCCCAACAUUAUAACAAGGGAUAUGGGAGUUAUAAGCCAGGAACUGUGGAUGGAAACCAAUGACAGAUAUCAUAAUAUCACACCCACACAUCAGGCAAGAGACUUGUUCCUUAAAAAUUAUCUAGUUUAGCCGAGCGUGGUGGCUCACACCUGUAAUCCCAGCUACUUGGGAGGCUGAGGCAGGAGAAUCACUUGAACCCAGGAGGUGGAGGUUGCAGCAAGCAGAGAUCACACCACUGCACUACAGCCUCGGCAAUAGAGCGAGACUCUGUGUCAAAAAAAAAAAAA